AAUCUGCAGCAGAGAUUUACCCGAGCGUGUUGCGGCAGCGGCUGGGCUUGCAAGGCGCGAUCCAAGAGGGAUUUAAGCAGCCCAGAGCUCCAGAGAAAAAGAGAGCGAGAGAGAACCACACACAGAGACGGCUUAAGCGUUUACCCGAAUUAAAUAUAUAUUUUUAAAAAGAACUGUUGAGUUUUAUCAUUUUCGUUAAGUGACCGUGCGCAGCGCUGUAACUGCAGGAUGGGGAAGCAGAAUAGCAAACUGGCCCCUGAAGUGAUGGAGGACCUGGUGAAGAGCACAGAGUUUAAUGAGCAUGAACUCAAGCAGUGGUACAAAGGAUUUCUCAAGGACUGUCCAAGUGGGAGGCUAAAUCUCGAGGAAUUUCAGCAGCUCUAUGUGAAGUUCUUUCCUUAUGGAGACGCCUCCAAGUUUGCCCAGCAUGCCUUCCGAACCUUCGACAAGAAUGGGGACGGCACCAUUGACUUCCGAGAGUUCAUCUGCGCUCUGUCCAUCACCUCCAGGGGCAGCUUUGAGCAGAAGCUGAACUGGGCCUUCAAUAUGUAUGACCUGGAUGGUGAUGGCAAGAUCACCCGAGUGGAGAUGCUGGAGAUCAUCGAGCACAGUGCUGGGGAGGUCCCAGAACCAAGCCAUGGGGCCCGUACUGUCGUGACGGUGGCAUUGUCAUCUGCCAUUCACUCACUACUGGAUCUCCCACGAACCUGUCUUACUGUGCACACAGGAUGUCAUGGGCUGUUUCUCUGGCACUUGGUGUAUCUCUGCUCUGCCUCACUCCAGCUGCGCCUAGUGGGGACCCGAGGCUGUCAGGGGCUCCCGGGACAUCCUUCCAGGCUAUCUACAAAAUGGUAGGCACUGUGAUCAUGAUGAAAAUGAAUGAGGAUGGCCUGACGCCUGAGCAGCGAGUAGACAAGAUUUUCAGCAAGAUGGAUAAGAACAAAGAUGACCAGAUUACACUGGAUGAAUUCAAAGAAGCUGCAAAGAGCGACCCUUCCAUUGUAUUACUUCUGCAGUGCGACAUCCAGAAAUGAGCUGAUGUCAAUGCUAUGGACUGCACAAAAGUCUCAAUGUUCCAUUCAGUCUGCAGCUAUUCACACACACACACACACACACACACACACACACACACACACACACAAAUAUUGCUUGGACUACCUAUAAAUGGACUUGCUUCUUGUGUUUGAAACACUCGUGUGCAUGAGAAUGUCAUUUGCUAAUGAAUUUUAAAAGCAUAUAUAAAACAAAACAAACAACCUGCCACAAUGUGAUAUGUGUAAUAUCAUUUCAUAAAAAUCCCUCUUCCUCCAAAGCCUGGGCAGAAAUGUGCUGCAAAGAGUUAUAUGACUUCUUGUUCAUGUUUUGCUAAUGCUCGUAUCUCCUUGAUUACAUAAUGUUAGUAGCACUGAGACCCCCAUGGUAAUGUAACUUAAUUAUAAGCUAUGUCACUACCCUCCUGUAAAAUACUAUUGGACAGACACAGAGGGACCCUUGGCUCCUGUGUCUGGUCCACACACCACAGAAGCUUGUAUUAUCAGUGAAUAUAAAUGUACUACAUUUGCAUGCCUUUUGGGUUUGCCUUAAUUCUUACCUCAUUUGCAUCCUAUCGAUCUGGAAAGAGCUGUUUUGGAUGAAUGCAGUAUAAAAUGUAAAAACCCUGCUAAAUGACUUAUUGAUUAAGUAUAUCUAUCUAUAUAUACAUAUACACAAAGAUAUUAUUUAUCGAAAGUAAAAAAGAUGGAAGUGUAUUGGUUUCUGUUUGAAUUUUCAAAGGCUUCCAAUGUGGUGGCAAUAAAUGUCCCAAAUAAAUUUAUAACAAUUGAUUUUCCCCCUAAUUCUUAUUUUAUAAUUUUAAAAUUGCAGCAGUUGCUAGCAACAACUUACUAAAUCUACUCUUAAAUAUACAACUUUGGAAUUUGAAGAAUUAAUGACAACAAAAGGGAAAAAAGCAACUUUCCAACUUUUCAUCCAGGCUCCCAAAAGAGGGACAACGAACAUGGCAUGUGAAAAGUAAAACAGAUUUGUUCAUUCCGAAAAAAAAAUGUUCAUUCUAUGACAAUAAAUUUUAUCUCAGUGUGACUUUGGUGCUAACAACGUAUGUUCAGUGCAACUACGUGGAGCUGUGCACACACAGCAGGUAGGCUGCAGGUGUCCCCCAACAUAAGUCAGUAGGAAAGAAGACAUCUGUCUUCCCAAAUCUAAAGUAGGCAAAAAAUAACAGAAGUAGCUAUUUUUAAUAACAGAACAGAACUCUGACUCUUUUGAUCUUGAAGGAGGCAGAAGAGAUUCCAUCAAAACCUCUAAAAGCAGGUUUGCAUUUUCAGAACAUGCCCCCCUAGAGAGUUGAGUUUUUUACACAGCACUACCCGGUAGUACUUUCUCUGAUGAUGGGAAGGUCUACAUCUGCACAGCACGCUAGCUAUAACUGCACAUAUGGCUACUGAGCACUUCAAGUAUGGCUAGCGUGACUAAGGAACUGAAUUUUAUACUGUAAUUAAGUGUAAUUUGCCACAUAUAGCUAGUGGCUUUAGUAACAGACAGUUUAGUGCUAUAUUAUUUAUUCAAGUACUUUUUAUCAAAUUCGUUUUUUACCGAAUUCGUUUUUUACCAUUCUUUAUUUGUCUUAGGAUCAUUACAUAACACUAAACUAGGGUCUAA